AGCUGCUGCUGUCUCAGCCGCUCCACAGCGACGGCAGCGGCUGCGGCUUAGUCGGUGGCGGCCGGCGGCGGCUGCGGGCUGAGCGGCGAGUUUCCGAUUUAAAGCUGAGCUGCGAGGAAAAUGGCGGCGGGAGGAUCAAAAUACUUGCUGGAUGGUGGACUCAGAGACCAAUAAAAAUAAACUGCUUGAACAUCCUUUGACUGGUUAGCCAGUUGCUGAUGUAUAUUCAAGAUGAGUGGAUUAGGAGAAAACUUGGAUCCACUGGCCAGUGAUUCACGAAAACGCAAAUUGCCAUGUGAUACUCCAGGACAAGGUCUUACCUGCAGUGGUGAAAAACGGAGACGGGAGCAGGAAAGUAAAUAUAUUGAAGAAUUGGCUGAGCUGAUAUCUGCCAAUCUUAGUGAUAUUGACAAUUUCAAUGUCAAACCAGAUAAAUGUGCGAUUUUAAAGGAAACAGUAAGACAGAUACGUCAAAUAAAAGAGCAAGGAAAAACUAUUUCCAAUGAUGAUGAUGUUCAAAAAGCCGAUGUAUCUUCUACAGGGCAGGGAGUUAUUGAUAAAGACUCCUUAGGACCGCUUUUACUUCAGGCAUUGGAUGGUUUCCUAUUUGUGGUGAAUCGAGACGGAAACAUUGUAUUUGUAUCAGAAAAUGUCACACAAUACCUGCAAUAUAAGCAAGAGGACCUGGUUAACACAAGUGUUUACAAUAUCUUACAUGAAGAAGACAGAAAGGAUUUUCUUAAGAAUUUACCAAAAUCUACAGUUAAUGGAGUUUCCUGGACAAAUGAGACCCAAAGACAAAAAAGCCAUACAUUUAAUUGCCGUAUGUUGAUGAAAACACCACAUGAUAUUCUGGAAGACAUAAACGCCAGUCCUGAAAUGCGCCAGAGAUAUGAAACAAUGCAGUGCUUUGCCCUGUCUCAGCCACGAGCUAUGAUGGAGGAAGGGGAAGAUUUGCAAUCUUGUAUGAUCUGUGUGGCACGCCGCAUUACUACAGGAGAAAGAACAUUUCCAUCAAACCCUGAGAGCUUUAUUACCAGACAUGAUCUUUCAGGAAAGGUUGUCAAUAUAGAUACAAAUUCACUGAGAUCCUCCAUGAGGCCUGGCUUUGAAGAUAUAAUCCGAAGGUGUAUUCAGAGAUUUUUUAGUCUAAAUGAUGGGCAGUCAUGGUCCCAGAAACGUCACUAUCAAGAAGCUUAUCUUAAUGGCCAUGCAGAAACCCCAGUAUAUCGAUUCUCGUUGGCUGAUGGAACUAUAGUGACUGCACAGACAAAAAGCAAACUCUUCCGAAAUCCUGUAACAAAUGAUCGACAUGGCUUUGUCUCAACCCACUUCCUUCAGAGAGAACAGAAUGGAUAUAGACCAAACCCAAAUCCUGUUGGACAAGGGAUUAGACCACCUAUGGCUGGAUGCAACAGUUCGGUAGGCGGCAUGAGUAUGUCGCCAAACCAAGGCUUACAGAUGCCGAGCAGCAGGGCCUAUGGCUUGGCAGACCCUAGCACCACAGGGCAGAUGAGUGGAGCUAGGUAUGGGGGUUCCAGUAACAUAGCUUCAUUGACCCCUGGGCCAGGCAUGCAAUCACCAUCUUCCUACCAGAACAACAACUAUGGGCUCAACAUGAGUAGCCCCCCACAUGGGAGUCCUGGUCUUGCCCCAAACCAGCAGAAUAUCAUGAUUUCUCCUCGUAAUCGUGGGAGUCCAAAGAUAGCCUCACAUCAGUUUUCUCCUGUUGCAGGUGUGCACUCUCCCAUGGCAUCUUCUGGCAAUACUGGGAACCACAGCUUUUCCAGCAGCUCUCUCAGUGCCCUGCAAGCCAUCAGUGAAGGUGUGGGGACUUCCCUUUUAUCUACUCUGUCAUCACCAGGCCCCAAAUUGGAUAACUCUCCCAAUAUGAAUAUUACCCAACCAAGUAAAGUAAGCAAUCAGGAUUCCAAGAGUCCUCUGGGCUUUUAUUGCGACCAAAAUCCAGUGGAGAGUUCAAUGUGUCAGUCAAAUAGCAGAGAUCACCUCAGUGACAAAGAAAGUAAGGAGAGCAGUGUUGAGGGGGCAGAGAAUCAAAGGGGUCCUUUGGAAAGCAAAGGUCAUAAAAAAUUACUGCAGUUACUUACCUGUUCUUCUGAUGACCGGGGUCAUUCCUCCUUGACCAACUCCCCCCUAGAUUCAAGUUGUAAAGAAUCUUCUGUUAGUGUCACCAGCCCCUCUGGAGUCUCCUCCUCUACAUCUGGAGGAGUAUCCUCUACAUCCAAUAUGCAUGGGUCACUGUUACAAGAGAAGCACCGGAUUUUGCACAAGUUGCUGCAGAAUGGGAAUUCACCAGCUGAGGUAGCCAAGAUUACUGCAGAAGCCACUGGGAAAGACACCAGCAGUAUAACUUCUUGUGGGGACGGAAAUGUUGUCAAGCAGGAGCAGCUAAGUCCUAAGAAGAAGGAGAAUAAUGCACUUCUUAGAUACCUGCUGGACAGGGAUGAUCCUAGUGAUGCACUCUCUAAAGAACUACAGCCCCAAGUGGAAGGAGUGGAUAAUAAAAUGAGUCAGUGCACCAGCUCCACCAUUCCUAGCUCAAGUCAAGAGAAAGACCCUAAAAUUAAGACAGAGACAAGUGAAGAGGGAUCUGGAGACUUGGAUAAUCUAGAUGCUAUUCUUGGUGAUCUGACUAGUUCUGACUUUUACAAUAAUUCCAUAUCCUCAAAUGGUAGUCAUCUGGGGACUAAGCAACAGGUGUUUCAAGGAACUAAUUCUCUGGGUUUGAAAAGUUCACAGUCUGUGCAGUCUAUUCGUCCUCCAUAUAACCGAGCAGUGUCUCUGGAUAGCCCUGUUUCUGUUGGCUCAAGUCCUCCAGUAAAAAAUAUCAGUGCUUUCCCCAUGUUACCAAAGCAACCCAUGUUGGGUGGGAAUCCAAGAAUGAUGGAUAGUCAGGAAAAUUAUGGCUCAAGUAUGGGUGGGCCAAACCGAAAUGUGACUGUGACUCAGACUCCUUCCUCAGGAGACUGGGGCUUACCAAACUCAAAGGCCGGCAGAAUGGAACCUAUGAAUUCAAACUCCAUGGGAAGACCAGGAGGAGAUUAUAAUACUUCUUUACCCAGACCUGCACUGGGUGGCUCUAUUCCCACAUUGCCUCUUCGGUCUAAUAGCAUACCAGGUGCGAGACCAGUAUUGCAACAGCAGCAGCAGAUGCUUCAAAUGAGGCCUGGUGAAAUCCCCAUGGGAAUGGGGGCUAAUCCCUAUGGCCAAGCAGCAGCAUCUAACCAACUGGGUUCCUGGCCCGAUGGCAUGUUGUCCAUGGAACAAGUUUCUCAUGGCACUCAAAAUAGGCCUCUUCUUAGGAAUUCCCUGGAUGAUCUUGUUGGGCCACCUUCCAACCUGGAAGGCCAGAGUGACGAAAGAGCAUUAUUGGACCAGCUGCACACUCUUCUCAGCAACACAGAUGCCACAGGCCUGGAAGAAAUUGACAGAGCUUUGGGCAUUCCUGAACUUGUCAAUCAGGGACAGGCAUUAGAGCCCAAACAGGAUGCUUUCCAAGGCCAAGAAGCAGCAGUAAUGAUGGAUCAGAAGGCAGGAUUAUAUGGACAGACAUACCCAGCACAGGGGCCUCCAAUGCAAGGAGGCUUUCAUCUUCAGGGACAAUCACCAUCUUUUAACUCUAUGAUGAAUCAGAUGAACCAGCAAGGCAAUUUUCCUCUCCAAGGAAUGCACCCACGAGCCAACAUCAUGAGACCCCGGACAAACACCCCCAAGCAACUUAGAAUGCAGCUUCAGCAGAGGCUGCAGGGCCAGCAGUUUUUGAAUCAGAGCCGACAGGCACUUGAAUUGAAAAUGGAAAACCCUACUGCUGGUGGUGCUGCGGUGAUGAGGCCUAUGAUGCAGCCCCAGGUGAGCUCCCAGCAGGGUUUUCUUAAUGCUCAAAUGGUCGCCCAACGCAGCAGAGAGCUGCUAAGUCAUCACUUCCGACAACAGAGGGUGGCUAUGAUGAUGCAGCAGCAGCAGCAGCAGCAACAGCAGCAGCAGCAGCAGCAGCAGCAGCAACAGCAACAGCAACAGCAACAGCAGCAACAGCAGCAAACCCAGGCCUUCAGCCCACCUCCUAAUGUGACUGCUUCCCCCAGCAUGGAUGGGCUUUUGGCAGGACCCACAAUGCCACAAGCUCCUCCGCAACAGUUUCCAUAUCAACCAAAUUAUGGAAUGGGACAACAACCAGAUCCAGCCUUUGGUCGAGUGUCUAGUCCUCCCAAUGCAAUGAUGUCGUCAAGAAUGGGUCCCUCCCAGAAUCCCAUGAUGCAACACCCGCAGGCUGCAUCCAUCUAUCAGUCCUCAGAAAUGAAGGGCUGGCCAUCAGGAAAUUUGGCCAGGAACAGCUCCUUUUCCCAGCAGCAGUUUGCCCACCAGGGGAAUCCUGCAGUGUAUAGUAUGGUGCACAUGAAUGGCAGCAGUGGUCACAUGGGACAGAUGAACAUGAACCCCAUGCCCAUGUCUGGCAUGCCUAUGGGUCCUGAUCAGAAAUACUGCUGACAUCUCUGCACCAGGACCUCUUAAGGAAACCACUGUACAAAUGACACUGCACUAGGAUUAUUGGGAAGGAAUCAUUGUUCCAGGCAUCCAUCUUGGAAGAAAGGACCAGCUUUGAGCUCCAUCAAGGGUAUUUUAAGUGAUGUCAUUUGAGCAGGACUGGAUUUUAAGCCGAAGGGCAAUAUCUACGUGUUUUUCCCCCCUCCUUCUGCUGUGUAUCAUGGUGUUCAAAACAGAAAUGUUUUUUGGCAUUCCACCUCCUAGGGAUAUAAUUCUGGAGACAUGGAGUGUUACUGAUCAUAAAACUUUUGUGUCACUUUUUUCUGCCUUGCUAGCCAAAAUCUCUUAAAUACACGUAGGUGGGCCAGAGAACAUUGGAAGAAUCAAGAGAGAUUAGAAUAUCUGGUUUCUCUAGUUGCAGUAUUGGACAAAGAGCAUAGUCCCAGCCUUCAGGUGUAGUAGUUCUGUGUUGACCCUUUGUCCAGUGGAAUUGGUGAUUCUGAAUUGUCCUUUACUAAUGGUGUUGAGUUGCUCUGUCCCUAUUAUUUGCCCUAGGCUUUCUCCUAAUGAAGGUUUUCAUUUGCCAUUCAUGUCCUGUAAUACUUCACCUCCAGGAACUGUCAUGGAUGUCCAAAUGGCUUUGCAGAAAGGAAAUGAGAUGACAGUAUUUAAUCGCAGCAGUAGCAAACUUUUCACAUGCUAAUGUGCAGCUGAGUGCACUUUAUUUAAAAAGAAUGGAUAAAUGCAAUAUUCUUGAGGUCUUGAGGGAAUAGUGAAACACAUUCCUGGUUUUUGCCUACACUUACGUGUUAGACAAGAACUAUGAUUUUUUUUUUUAAAGUACUGGUGUCACCCUUUGCCUAUAUGGUAGAGCAAUAAUGCUUUUUAAAAAUAAACUUCUGAAAACCCAAGGCCAGGUACUGCAUUCUGAAUCAGAAUCUCGCAGUGUUUCUGUGAAUAGAUUUUUUUGUAAAUAUGACCUUUAAGAUAUUGUAUUAUGUAAAAUAUGUAUAUACCUUUUUUUGUAGGUCACAACAACUCAUUUUUACAGAGUUUGUGAAGCUAAAUAUUUAACAUUGUUGAUUUCAGUAAGCUGUGUGGUGAGGCUACCAGUGGAAGAGACAUCCCUUGACUUUUGUGGCCUGGGGGAGGGGUAGUGCUCCACAGCUUUUCCUUCCCCACCCCCCAGCCUUAGAUGCCUCGCUCUUUUCAAUCUCUUAAUCUAAAUGCUUUUUAAAGAGAUUAUUUGUUUAGAUGUAGGCAUUUUAAUUUUUUAAAAAUUCCUCUACCAGAACUAAGCACUUUGUUAAUUUGGGGGGAAAGAAUAGAUAUGGGGAAAUAAACUUAAAAAAAAAUCAGGAAUUUAAAAAAACGAGCAAUUUGAAGAGAAUCUUUUGGAUUUUAAGCAGUCCGAAAUAAUAGCAAUUCAUGGGCUGUGUGUGUGUGUGUAUGUGUGUGUGUGUGUGUGUAUGUUUAAUUAUGUUACCUUUUCAUCCCCUUUAGGAGCGUUUUCAGAUUUUGGUUGCUAAGACCUGAAUCCCAUAUUGAGAUCUCGAGUAGAAUCCUUGGUGUGGUUUCUGGUGUCUGCUCAGCUGUCCCCUCAUUCUACUAAUGUGAUGCUUUCAUUAUGUCCCUGUGGAUUAGAAUAGUGUCAGUUAUUUCUUAAGUAACUCAGUACCCAGAACAGCCAGUUUUACUGUGAUUCAGAGCCACAGUCUAACUGAGCACCUUUUAAACCCCUCCCUCUUCUGCCCCCUACCACUUUUCUGCUGUUGCCUCUCUUUGACACCUGUUUUAGUCAGUUGGGAGGAAGGGAAAAAUCAAGUUUAAUUCCCUUUAUCUGGGUUAAUUCAUUUGGUUCAAAUAGUUGACGGAAUUGGGUUUCUGAAUGUCUGUGAAUUUCAGAGGUCUCUGCUAGCCUUGGUAUCAUUUUCUAGCAAUAACUGAGAGCCAGUUAAUUUUAAGAAUUUCACACAUUUAGCCAAUCUUUCUAGAUGUCUCUGAAGGUAAGAUCAUUUAAUAUCUUUGAUAUGCUUACGAGUAAGUGAAUCCUGAUUAUUUCCAGACCCACCACCAGAGUGGAUCUUAUUUUCAAAGCAGUAUAGACAAUUAUGAGUUUGCCCUCUUUCCCCUACCAAGUUCAAAAUAUAUCUAAGAAAGAUUGUAAAUCCGAAAACUUCCAUUGUAGUGGCCUGUGCUUUUCAGAUAGUAUACUCUCCUGUUUGGAGACAGAGGAAGAACCAGGUCAGUCUGUCUCUUUUUCAGCUCAAUUGUAUCUGACCCUUCUUUAAGUUAUGUGUGUGGGGAGAAAUAGAAUGGUGCUCUUAUCUUUCUUGACUUUAAAAAAAUUAUUAAAAACAAAAAAAAAAUAAAUUUUUUUGCAAUCCUUUCCUCAGACCUGGCUCCAGGCUAACUGGAAGGCAGCACUCCCUUUUUUAUAUAGUAGAAAAAUGAAGUUUAUUAUAAGUUUUUAUAUUUUCUACUUGUUCAUUUGGUGCAAACUCAAGAUUUCUUUUAAUAGGUGCAGUCUUUGAGAUAAUUUGUUUUUACCUGUAUUGCCCUUUAUCUUUUUUAGGUAAUUCUUUGUACUCCUGCUGUCUACCUCUCCUCACACCCCAGCACCCCCCAUUUUUUCAAACCUUGGUAUCUGUUGGGUGAACAGUAUAAUCUUUUCAUCUGCUUUUAGAAUGUGGGAUAUUUCCAGUACCUACUUUUUUUUUUUUUUUUUGCUGAAUCCAAAGAUAUAUAAAUAAAAUAUAUAUAUUUUAUAAAGAUCAGAAUGAUAUAAAGGAGAUACAUGUUUCUUCCUUUAAAAAAUAAACGGAAGUUACAUUGUUAAUGUUCAUAUUAUGAUGCCACUUUUCUAAACUGCAUCUGGAUUGAAAGGUGUAAAUAUCAAUAACAGUGCUACUUAGUUAUCAGUAUUUAAUAUCUGAGGUGAGUUGGGGGUAUCUAUAUUAGGGGUAGGGUAUUACAGAAGAUAAUUGGCUUGAUGUCCUAGAAGUUCUUUGAUCCAGAGGUGGGUGCAGCUGAAAGUAAACAGAAUGGAUUGCCAGUUACAUGUAUGCCUGCCCAGUUCCCUUUUUAUUUGCAGAAGCUGUGAGUUUUGUUCACAAUUAGGUUCCUAGGAGCAAAACCUCAAGGAUUGAUUUAUUGUUUUCAACUCCAAGGCACACUGUUAAUAAACGAGCAGGGUGUUUUCUCUCUUCCUUUCUAAUAUAUGGAGUUUCGAAGAAUAAAAUAUGAGAGCAAUAUUUAAAUUCUCAGGAAUUGACUUAUACUCUUGAGAAUGAAUUCAGUUUCAAUCAAGUUUACAUUAUGUUGCUUAAAAAAAUAGAAAUUAUUCUUUAUCUUGCAAAGAAUUGAAACCACAUGAAAUGACUUAUGGGGGAUGGUGAGCUGUGACUGCUUUGCUGACCAUUUUGGAUGUCAUUGUAAAUAAAGGUUUCUAUUUAAAA